AGCAUCGCGGAGUCGGUGCUUUAGUACGCCGCUGGCACCUUUACUCUCGCCGGCCGCGCGAACCCGUUUGAGCUCGGUAUCCUAGUGCACACGCCUUGCAAGCGACGGCGCCAUGAGUCUGACUUCCAGUUCCAGCGUACGAGUUGAAUGGAUCGCAGCAGUUACCAUUGCUGCUGGGACAGCUGCAAUUGGUUAUCUAGCUUACAAAAGAUUUUAUGUUAAAGAUCAUCGAAAUAAAGCUAUGAUAAACCUUCACAUCCAGAAAGACAACCCCAAGAUAGUACAUGCUUUUGACAUGGAGGAUUUGGGAGAUAAAGCUGUGUACUGCCGUUGUUGGAGGUCCAAAAAGUUCCCAUUCUGUGAUGGGGCUCACACAAAACAUAACGAAGAGACUGGAGACAAUGUGGGCCCUCUGAUCAUCAAGAAAAAAGAAACUUAAAUGGACACUUUUGAUGCUGCAAAUCAGCUUGUCGUGAAGUUACCUGAUUGUUUAAUUAGAAUGACUACCACCUCUGUCUGAUUCACCUUCGCUGGAUUCUAAAUGUGGUAUAUUGCAAACUGCAGCUUUCACAUUUAUGGCAUUUGUCUUGUUGAAACAUCGUGGUGCACAUUUGUUUAAACAAAAAAAAAAAAAAAAAGGAAAAACCAACCUGCAUGGCCUGUGGGUUAUUUUGGUCUUGUAAGGAUCCAUUUCUUUAAAAUACUGACAUAUAGAGUUGUACCUUAUAUAGAAUAUAGUUGUAUCUUGAAGUCAACAUAUUAAAUUAUUCUCAAAAUUAUGUAUUUGCAGAUUGUACUUGUAAGUUUCAAAGAAAAAUUACCAUCUUUUCAUAUUGACCUGGAAACUAAAUAGGAUGUGAUUCAGCUACAUUAAUUUCUUAAUACAAUCUAGGAAAGACCUGUUGUAGCCUUGAUUUUCUUGACAUUGGUAAUGACACUGAGAAAAUAUGGCUUCUGUUUUUCACCGUUUUCAAUCAAAAUGAUUGAUAAAUGUUAUUCUGUUUAAUUUCAUAAGUCAGGUCAAUAAUAAAGGGGUGGUAACUUCCUCAUAUUUAUCUUCACAGAUAUUUAAUGAAGAUGGAUCCAUUAAAGGAGCCAAUAGUGAAAAUUUAGUUAAAGGUGAUAUUAGAUUUAAAUUAGUCAUGAAGAAUGUCUUAAAAUCUAAUGUUCCAGAAUUCUGGCCCAAGGAAUGGUAAGCACUUGAACUGAGGAUUUUGAAGGAAUUGGAACAUAUAAUGUCAAGUCUUUUGAUCACUAAGCCACAUAUCCUGACAGAAAUAGUAGUCACAAGAUUAGAUCAAAGGCGUGGGAAGAUUUUUUUUUUUCCCACUCUAGCUAAUCAAGCACAUGGCUUUUAAAUUGUAUGAUCUUUUUCUUAAAAGCAAAAAUUUGAAGACAAGUGUUUGUUUAUGUAAUAUUCUUCAAAGACUCCGAGCAGAAACAUUGCAUUCAUUGUUGAUUCAGAAAAAAGAAAAUAUAAAAACUGAAAAUAAUUAGCAAUAAAAGAUUUAAGACAAAUAGUUCAUAAAUAUUUUUAAAGAGAUUAGGUUUUUGAAUUUCAUAGGUUAGAAGGAAAAUCAUGGCAAAAUUUACAGAAAAUUGGGCAAACAAUUGAAAUUGAUAAAGCAGGUAAACAUCAUCAUUUAUUUUAGUAUACAUGAAUUCUCAGUAGUAGUCAAUCACAAAUUUCUACUUGCUAAAAUCCAUUUACCUUGACAGGAAUCAAACCUGACAGCAGCAUAUCCUAUGUAAUAUAUGAUCAUGGCUAUUUUUAAAUAUGUAGUUUUGUGUAUUACUGUAGAUAAAAGUUGGUAACAAAAUUGUACAGUGGUUUUAAGAAGCCCAUGUAACUAACUUGGACAUGUCUUUAAGUCACAUAUUCAUCAUAAAAUCUAAAAUCCUACAAACUGAUUCUAUUAGAUUCUUAGGGUAAAUUUUUUCUUUGCCCACCUCCUUCUUUUUAAGAUAAGUAUGCAUGUCAGCAAAACAGAGCAAUCAUGCUUUUAAAGAUGAACUGUUUUAAAGAAAAAUAAAUGCAUCAACUCCCAGUGUUUCUGAUAAAGGGACAUCCUUCUAACUUAACAGACUAUUCUUUAUCUUGAAUUUGAAAUUAUAUUGUUAGUCAUGCAUUUUUGUAAUGUCAGGGGGAACCUGGUACCAGUUCUCAAAACUAUAGGAUUAUAUGAGUGUGUGUAUACAUAUGGCAAAAUUAUAAAUGACCACCUUACUGUGAAAUAUAGAUCUUGAGCAUUUUGAAAGGCCAAAAUAAUUAGGUAAAUGUAUUUUCAAGGUCAUGUUAAAAUGUUUACAUGCUUUUGAACUAGCAUUCAUUUAUGAUUAAAACCCUUUUCAGGUUAUUUGACCUAAAAACCAAA